AACAACAGCUGAGUCAGACAGAUGAUCUGUACACUGUUUUAUACCAAGAAAUCAUUUACAAUGAAGAUCCUUCUCUUUUUCUGUAUUUUGCUUUUCUUUGGAGUCCUUAUUCCACCAGCCAGAAGUGAAGGGCACCAUAUCACCUUUAGUAGGUGGAAGUCAUGUACAGCGAUUGGAGGUCGAUGUAAAAAUCAAUGUGAUGAUAGUGAAUUUAGGAUUUCAUACUGUGCAAGACCUACAACUCAUUGCUGCGUGACAGAAUGUGACCCUACGGACCCAAAUAAUUGGAUCCCAAAGGACUCAGUAGGGACUCAAGAAUGGUACCCUAAAGACUCACGUCAUUGAAGAAAUCCAUGCACAAGAAGAUGAUACAUCUGAAUGAAGUCCUCUCAUUAUUUCAUCACUUCAUUAAUGACCUAUAAUUUCCAUGCAUGCAUACCUAUAAUGAAUAAAUAAUUAAAUAAAAUAUAUUUCAGCUGGACAUUUUUAUAAACAUUGUGCUUGCUUAGAAGAAAGAAUCAGAAUACAAAGCAGGGAUUUGAACUCUGGAAUAGAAGCAGCGUGGAGAAGAAAAUCCAUGAUGGGACCGCUAAGUUUAGUGAGAUUCUGGGGCCAAUUCCUUAUUUAGUGUGAAAAGCAUAUUAUGAGUCAUUAGUGAGGUAUUAUCAAGAAUUCUUUGAGGAGACUCAGGAGUGGGGACAGAGUUGAUAAGAGAUGUGACCCCUGAACUAGUAAAAAUCGUUGCAAGAAAUUUGAAGGAUUAUGAAAUCCUCAUAACUUUCUCAUAUUGCUUAUACUUCCUGGUUAUACUUUUUCUCUCUUUUUUGAAAGAAUUAUGAAAAUAAAAAUAACUGAUUUUUUUUCCAAGAAUAAUCUCAAAAGGUAGAAUAGAGGGAGACUAGGUUGAGGAAGGAAAAGAAGAAUGGUAAAUCCCUGUAGCUUGUGGCAAUAACGAUAAUGUGAAAUUAUGAUUAACUUUUUUGUUUUGUUUUGCUUUGUUUCAUGUUUUUAAUGUUUCCACAUAUUAUCAGAUGAUUCUUAUCAUGCUACUUAUUGGUGUCUUAGUAAAUUUUAAGUUUUUAAAAAAUAAUGUAACAGAAUUAUAUAUGUGUGUAUGCAUGCUCACACAUAUAAUUUCUAUUAUAGAAAUUUUUGUCAUACCCAGGAUUUAUGUGGCAAGGAUGUGUUAACAAAGGCUAAAUUGUGGCCUUGAGGGAAAGGGUCAGCAGUUGGUCUUAAUACCUCACCUAGAUUAAAGAUUUUCCCCUUAUUCAAACAUUUUGAAAUAUCAACUCUAAAAAUAGGUGAUGGUUUUGCAGGGCUUGGUAUGUGCUAAGUAUUACUUAAAGAAUGUCCUCUAGGCUUUGUCCUUGGCUGGCAGCCUUGGUUAUUAUGUGACUUACAACCUGUGGACUAAGGCCACAUGAAGAAAAGGGAGCUAGUCACUUAAAAUUAUGUGGUAACAAGGUAUUUAAGUUGAGGCUACUUGUACCUGGUAGGUUUCUUAUGCUGCUGUGACAUAUACACAUUUCAGCUUUGGGUUAAUCUUAUAACCAAAACAUAUCCUGUACACAGUACCUGGGCACAUAGGGAAAAGCAUCUGGGUGUCCAAAUUAUAUAUGAUAUUCCUGAUAUGUAUAAUACUAUGCUCUCUGACCAGUGUCAAUUUGGAGCUAAAUAACCCUAUUUGCAUCUUGUGAUUUUGGUUUAUGAUCCAAACUCUGAACCCCACUUCAGGGGUCUCACAGUAUACCUAUACUAUAAUUUAAUGUAUCUGUGGUAGGAUAGAUGAAAAUUAUGAAUAAAGCUGCUAUAAUUGUA